GCAGAGGAGGGCGGUGUUGAGACCGGCGGAGCGGCGGGACCCCUAGGUGGCGGAGGGACGCUCCGGGAAAGCGAGGGGCGCUACGAGCUCUGGCCCACGUGACCUGCCGGGGGCGGGAGCAGGGGGCGCGCCGGCCUCCUGCGGUGCCCCUGCCUUGGGGAGGGGCCGUGACCACCCGUCUGUCGCCCGAGGCGGCCGCCGCUGCACCUUCACCGCGUACCCGGGACCCGCCCGCCCGCGGGAGAUAAAAACUAUACUAGAGUCCAGCGACUUCUUACCACUCUGAAUGUGAGUAACAAAUUGUGAAUCAAAGCCCGAAUCCCCGUGGAAUUCAUUCCGAGGCUGAUUGCAAUCACUUGGAGUCGGGCGCGUCCUACCUAAACCAGGCAGUUUAUGGCAAAUACCUGCCUUGACCGUGCUUAAAUUAGUGAACUUUUGGGCACCAACUGGUCGAUUUACCAUAGAAAUUGGUAGUUGCUGCAAAAAGAGGAACAAUGCCAAGGAAAAAAGUCUACAUGUUCAGUAGAGACACAACUUUUCAUUUUCUUUCCUGAAUAUUUUUGAUACGCGGUUGGUUGAAUCCACUAUGCAGAACCCACAGAUCUGGAGGACCUACUAUAAUUUAAUUUAAUUCUAAGAAAUGUUGCUGAAGUGCUGCUGAAAGGGCCAGAGAUGCAAGGAUUUGGGAUACAUUUUGAACCUUUAAGCUGUCUGACAUUGACCUCCUUUCAUUAUUAAUAAAGAAGAAUCAGGAGCUUAGGAUGUAUUAACACCAACUCAUUAAUAUACUAACCGGACAAUGUUCUACAAACAAUUCUACAUUGUAAAGGACUGGAUUGGCACAAAAUAAAAUAAUUUUAUUUUAUUCAGCUUAUAAUAUGACUCGAUGGAGGAAAAUUUGAUAAGCAUGAGAGAAGACCAUUCUUUUCAUGUUCGUUACAGAAUGGAAGCUUCUUGCCUAGAGCUGGCCUUGGAAGGGGAACGUCUAUGUAAAUCAGGAGACUGCCGCGCUGGCGUGUCAUUCUUUGAAGCUGCAGUUCAAGUUGGAACUGAAGACCUAAAAACACUUAGCGCUAUUUACAGCCAGUUGGGCAAUGCUUAUUUCUAUUUGCAUGAUUAUGCCAAAGCAUUAGAAUAUCACCAUCAUGAUUUAACCCUUGCAAGGACUAUUGGAGACCAGCUGGGGGAAGCGAAAGCUAGUGGUAAUCUGGGAAACACCUUAAAAGUUCUUGGGAAUUUUGACGAAGCCAUAGUUUGUUGUCAGCGACACCUAGAUAUUUCCAGAGAGCUUAAUGACAAGGUGGGAGAAGCAAGAGCACUUUACAAUCUUGGGAAUGUGUAUCAUGCCAAAGGGAAAAGUUUUGGUUGCCCUGGUCCCCAGGAUGUAGGAGAAUUUCCAGAAGAAGUGAGAGAUGCUCUGCAGGCAGCCGUGGAUUUUUAUGAGGAAAACCUAUCAUUAGUGACUGCUUUGGGUGACCGAGCGGCACAAGGACGUGCCUUUGGAAAUCUUGGAAACACACAUUACCUCCUUGGCAACUUCAGGGAUGCAGUUAUAGCUCAUGAGCAGCGUCUCCUUAUUGCAAAAGAAUUUGGAGAUAAAGCAGCUGAAAGAAGAGCAUAUAGCAACCUUGGAAAUGCAUAUAUAUUUCUUGGUGAAUUUGAAACUGCCUCGGAAUACUACAAGAAGACACUACUGUUGGCCCGACAGCUUAAAGACCGAGCUGUAGAAGCACAGUCUUGUUACAGUCUUGGAAAUACAUAUACUUUACUUCAAGACUAUGAAAAGGCCAUUGAUUAUCAUCUGAAGCACUUAGCAAUUGCUCAAGAGCUGAAUGAUAGAAUUGGUGAAGGAAGAGCAUGUUGGAGCUUAGGAAAUGCAUACACAGCACUAGGAAAUCAUGAUCAAGCAAUGCAUUUUGCUGAAAAGCACUUGGAAAUUUCAAGAGAGGUUGGGGAUAAAAGUGGUGAACUAACAGCACGACUUAAUCUCUCAGACCUUCAAAUGGUUCUUGGUCUGAGCUACAGCACAAAUAACUCCAUAAUGUCUGAAAAUACUGAAAUUGAUAGCAGUUUGAAUGGUGUACGCCCCAAGUUGGGACGCCGGCAUAGUAUGGAAAAUAUGGAACUUAUGAAGUUAACACCAGAAAAGGUACAGAACUGGAACAGUGAAAUUCUUGCUAAGCAAAAACCUCUUAUUGCCAAACCUUCUGCAAAGCUACUCUUUGUCAACAGACUGAAGGGGAAAAAAUACAAAACGAAUUCCUCCACUAAAGUUCUCCAAGAUGCCAGUAAUUCUAUUGACCACCGAAUUCCAAAUUCUCAGAGGAAAAUCAGUGCAGAUACUAUUGGAGAUGAAGGGUUCUUUGACUUAUUAAGCCGAUUUCAAAGCAAUAGGAUGGAUGAUCAGAGAUGUUGCUUACAAGAAAAGAACUGCCAUACAGCUUCAACAACAACUUCUUCCACUCCCCCUAAAAUGAUGCUAAAAACAUCAUCUGUUCCUGUGGUAUCCCCCAACACGGAUGAGUUUUUAGAUCUUCUUGCCAGCUCACAGAGUCGCCGUCUGGAUGACCAGAGGGCUAGUUUCAGUAAUUUGCCAGGGCUUCGUCUAACACAAAACAGCCAGUCGGUACUUAGCCACCUGAUGACUAAUGACAACAAAGAGGCUGAUGAAGAUUUCUUUGACAUCCUUGUAAAAUGUCAAGGAUCCAGAUUAGAUGAUCAAAGAUGUGCUCCACCACCUGCUACCACAAAGGGUCCGACAGUACCAGAUGAAGACUUUUUCAGCCUUAUUUUACGGUCCCAGGGAAAGAGAAUGGAUGAACAGAGAGUUCUUUUACAAAGAGAUCAAAACAGAGACACUGACUUUGGGCUAAAGGACUUUUUGCAAAAUAAUGCUUUGUUGGAGUUUAAAAAUUCAGGGAAAAAAUCGGCAGACCAUUAGUUACUAUGGAUUUAUUUUUUUUCCUUUCAAACACGGUAAGGAAACAAUCUAUUACUUUUUUCCUUAAAAGGAGAAUUUAUAGCACUGUAAUACAGCUUAAAAUAUUUUUAGAAUGAUGUAAAUAGUUAACCUUCAGUAGUCUAUUAAGGCAUUAAUACUUCUCUGGACAUGCGCGUUUGAGGGUGGAGGGGUCCUGUAAGGUGCUUCAUCGUCUGUGAUUACUGCUUGGGAUGUGUUCUUUGGCAGCUUGUGAGAUUACUUUACCUAGUGUUUAUAAAGUAGGAAGUUAAGUGAAUCAUAGAUUAGAAUUUAAUACUCUUAUGGAAAUAAUUUUUUAACAUCUUAAUUGACAAUGGCGUUUUUUUAUACAUAACCAUGGAUGUAGUGGGAAACAAUGUUGUUUGGUAAAAAUAAUGUACUUGAUCAAUGUAAAAAAGUAUAUAAAAUAGUCUUACUAAAAAUCUAGGUUUUUUUUUCCUCCAUGAAAAUCUGUUUUUUUAGGCCAAAGUCAGUAUAAAAGAAACUCUACUUCUUGGGCUGGGCAUGGUGGCUCAUUCCUGUAAUCCCAGCACAUUGGGAGGCUGAGGCAGGAGGAUCGCUUGAGGCUAGGAGUUCAAGACCAACCUGGGCAACAUAGACCCCCGUGUCUAUGAAAAAUAAAUCAGCAGCCAGGCGCAGUGGCUCACACCUGUAAUCCCAGCACUUUGGGAGGCCGAAGCGGGCGGAUCACUUGAGGUCGGGAGUUUGAGACCAGCCUGGCCAACAUAGUGAAACCCUGUCUCUACUAAAAAUACAAAAAUUAGCUGGGCAUGGUGGCAUGCGCCUGUAGUUUCAGCUACUUGGGAGGCUGAGGCAGGAGAAUCACUUGAACCCCUGGGAGGCAGAGAUUGCAGUGAGCUGAGACCAAGCCACUGGACUCCAGCCUGAGUGACAGAGCAAGACUCUGUCUCAAAAAAAAAAAAAACAGCAAGCAUGCUGGCACACACCUGUAGUCCCAACUGCUUAAGAGGCUGAGGCAGGAGGACCACUUGAGCCCAGGAGGUGGAGGCUGCACUGAGCUAUGAUCGUGCCACUGCACUCCAGCCUGGGUGACAGAGCAAGACCCUGUCUCUAGAAAACAAGUAUCUUUUGUGUGUUUUGGGCUGUUUAAAAAAAUUAUUUAAAAUGGUCUCUUCUGUUCCAUAAUACUGCUGUAAAACAAACUUUUCUAAGUUCUAAUAUAAAAACAAAAAACAAAACCCAUGUGGUUAGGUCAAGAACCUAGGACACAUAAACAAACAGAAAACAGAUGAAAACUCACAAAAAUUAAAUAUGAAAGAAAGAUGUCAGCUAGAACCUUAGUUGUCAUUAAGCUUUGUCUUCCUUAUCCCAGAUAUUGAAGGCAGUUUACAAGGGGAUGAUAACAAAGUAACUAACUAACUGUAGCAAAAGACAAGUAUGGGACAGACUGGGACCUGGAGUAACACUGGAUCACAGACUGCAAAGGCCCACGCUUGGAACAAGUUGCCAACUUGUUUCACUCUGCUUGCUUCAGACUGUGCACAGCUGGGAUGGGAUCUGGGGAUGUGGACCCCUAUUCUUUCAAAAAGUCAUUCAGGUGAUUUGGAUGGGCAAAUAGAACUAUUUCUCUAAUGGCCAAUGUUUUUUAAGAGUCAUAACCUGGAAUUAAUUACAUUAAGUGCUCAGCUAAAAAAAAAAAAAAAGUUCUAAAUUACAACCUGGAUUACAUUAUGUUUCAUGUAUACUAUAAGGUAUGAUGUCCUGGAUAGCAUUUUAAAAACUCAGGUAAGUUUCAUGGGGUUCUUAUAAGAAAAUUCAGUUAAGACAAUAUACCAAACCACAACGUAAAAAGUUUGUGUAUACAAACUUUUUGUAUUAUUUGUACACAAAGUACAAAUUUGUAUUUGUACACAAAGUACAAACUUUGUGUAUUAUUUUGUGUAUACAAUAGUUCUUACAGCCUGUAAACAUUCAACAUUAUUCCAUUUAAACAUUGUUUUUAACAGCUGUCUACCCUGUUCUGAUUUUCCUAAAAGCUUCACACUAUAUAGGCUGGGCACAAUGGCUCAUGCCUGUAAUCCCAGCACUUUGGGAGGCCGACAAGGGCGGGUCACUUGAGGUCAGGAGUUCGAGACCAGCCUGACCAACAUGGUGAAACCCCAUCUCUACUAAAAAAUACAAAAAUUAGCCAGGCAUGGUGAUGCACAUCUGUAAUCCUAGCUACUCGGGAGACUGAGGCAGGAGAAUCUCUUGAACCUGGGAGGUGGAGGUUGCAGUGAGCCGAGAUUGUACCACCUCACUCCAGCCUGGGUGACAGAGCAAAACUCUCAAAAAAAAGUAAAAUUUCAAAAAAGCUUCACAAUAUAAACCUUAAUUUUAAUGACAUAUUGGCUAGUCAAUAAACAAGUCUUAUCUCAUCUCAUCUCUUUUCUGAUAACAAACACCCGAUGUGUUCAAUUUGCUUUCAUAUUUAAGUCUUUCCUGAAUUGCUGUCAUCAUUCAACAACAGUUGCAUGUCGCCUUGCUAGCUGUCAAAGUAGACUUCAUCCCCAAAUGGAUAUCUGUAAUGAAAGAAUACAAAGGUGAAAUUUUAUUUAAAAAUUUUUUAAAAGAAUUUGGUUUUGGAUUAAAAGGCAUGCAAGCAGCAUUAAUUCCACUCACAGUUACAGUCUAUCACCUGGGGCAUUCACUACUUUUCAGAGUCAGAUCACAGUUCAAAAGACAGCUCUCACCUUGGGGGCAUAUUCCCCAAGUCAGUGUGAACAUGUCUUGUCCCAAGAGGACACUUUAUACGCAUGGAUGUUCACAAAUUUAUUCUAAACUGCAGGUGUCUGUCAGGAUUCAUUUGUUAAACAUGUCCUCUGUGUUAAAAAUCCUAAAAUCCUUUUGCAUUUCUUAGAAAAAAUCACGUUUCUGAUGAAAUUCUAAAGAUGUUUGCAAUAUUAAACUAGAAUAUAUUAACAUGUAUAAUUUUGAGACAAGGUCUUGCUCUGUCACCCAGGCUGGAGUACAGUGGCUCGAUCAUAACUCACUGCCACCUCACGAUCCUCUUGCCUCAGCCCUCCAAGUAGCUGGGACUACAGGCGUGUACCACCAUGCCUGGCUAGUUUUAUUUUUAGUACAUAGCCUUGAACAACUGAGCUUAAGCGAUCAUCCUCCCUCAACCUUCCAAAGUGCUAGGACUGUAGGCAUGAGCCACUGCACCUGGCCUAAAAUUACAUUGUUACAGGCACGUAAGUAACACUUCCUGGAUCCAAAAAUGUGUAUUCUGCAUUUCAACAACUGAACUUAAGCGAUCAUCCUCCCUCAACCUUCCAAAGUGCUAGGACUGUAGGCAUGAGCCACUGCACCUGGCCUAAAAUUACAUUGUUACAGGCACGUAAGUAACACUUCCUGGAUCCAAAAAUGUGUAUUCUGCAUUUCAACAACUGAACUUAAGCGAUCAUCCUCCCUCAACCUUCCAAAGUGCUAGGACUGUAGGCAUGAGCCACUGCACCUGGCCUAAAAUUACAUUGUUACAGGCACGUAAGUAACACUUCCUGGAUCCAAAAAUGUGUAUUCUGCAUUUCAUAUUAAAAUAAAAAAGCAAGUGCUUGGGAUACAAAUAUCUGCAUGAAAAUUUAAAGACUUUAUUCCUGACUGGUAUCACUUUUAGUAAGCAGUUGAACAUAACUUGUAGUGUGAAUAUGGUUAAAACAAAGGACACCUGAUGUCUGUGAAGUCUGCUAAGGACAGGUACAAAAUUUAUGCAUUGCUUUUUAAAAAGUUUAAAAUGAGGAAUGCUUUUGAUAAUCAGAAAGACUAAUGUAAAGUGCUGACUGAUGUCCUGUCUGCAGUUAAGGAAGACACCCAACUCUCUUCUUCCUCAUCAUGGUAUUCUCUAUGUAUAGAUCUCUAAAAAUGCAAACUUCCUAUGGACAAGACAAUAUGAUUUGCUAUAAUAUGAAUUAAGAUAUGGUAAUAUCUAAUAGUCUCCACUGCUAGGAUUCUGAGUAACACAAAAAAUAGGUUUUAUAAAAAGCCCAUGCACUUCAAUUGGUGGGGGAAAAGAAUAAAGUCAUUUUCAGUCGACUGACUCUGUAAAACAGAUUACCAAUAUAACAAGCUAUGUUAUCUAAAUUGCCCUGGCAGUCUUCAGUUUUCUCUAAGUAAACAAAGUAAAAGGAACAAUAAGGAUGCAGGCGUAGUAAUAGCUGUGGAAAAGAUGAAACUACAGCCACAGUGACCUGUGGGCAGCCUGCGUAGAGAUAAGCUGAGGUGUCAGUCAGACUGAUCCUGGUAACGAUACUCCAUGGCUGCAUGAAGAUGCUGGAGGCAUCAAGUGGGUGGCCUUAACUCUAGUGGAUUCACUAGGCAAUGUAAAUUGGUUAGUGGGUUCCCGUAAGUGCCUGUAACAAUAAAAUUUCUUUUUCAAUGUCCCCAAUUCAAACUGGCCUCCUUAACUAUCCAGAAUCAGUGAUGCCUGUCAUCUGUUCAUCUUAAAAUAAACACUUCUUACUUUAUGGGAUGUAAAUAUCAAAGAGAAGAUGAAAUGAAAAGCUUUUACAUAUAUAACGUGUUUGUUAAUUCUAAUUGUCAGUAAAAAUGUGAAUGUUGAAGUUGAAA